CCUUUCUCUCUCGCGCGCGGUGUGGUGGCAGCAGGCGCAGCCCAGCCUCGAAAUGCAGAACGACGCCGGCGAGUUCGUGGACCUGUACGUGCCGCGGAAAUGCUCCGCUAGCAAUCGCAUCAUCGGUGCCAAGGACCACGCAUCCAUCCAGAUGAACGUGGCCGAGGUUGACAAGGUCACAGGCAGGUUUAAUGGCCAGUUUAAAACUUAUGCUAUCUGCGGGGCCAUUCGUAGGAUGGGUGAGUCAGAUGAUUCCAUUCUCCGAUUGGCCAAGGCCGAUGGCAUCGUCUCAAAGAACUUUUGACUGGAGAGAAUCACAGAUGUGGAAUAUUUGUCAUAAAUAAAUAAUGAAAACCUA